GGCUGGCAGGUGGCGGAGAUUGCACCGGAAGACGCUUCCUGGGUUUGAGGAGUUCAGUGACUGCUAUUGAACCACCAAAAGUCCAUUAUGAAACUGUAUUGCCUGUCAGGGCACCCAACCUUACCAUGCAAUGUGCUCAAAUUCAAAUCAACCACCAUUAUGUUGGACUGCGGACUGGACAUGACUUCUACCCUCAAUUUCCUUCCUUUGCCACUUGUUCAAAGUCCCAGGCUGUCCAAUCUUCCUGGCUGGUCCCUGAAGGAUGGAAAUGCUUUCUUGGACAAGGAGCUAAAGGAGUGCUCGGGUCAUGUAUUUGUGGAUUCUGUGCCGGAAUUCUGUUUACCAGAGACGGAGCUAAUAGAUCUGUCUACAGUAGAUGUGAUUCUCAUCUCUAACUAUCACUGUAUGAUGGCGCUGCCAUACAUCACCGAGCACACCGGCUUCACAGGCACAGUGUAUGCCACGGAACCCACCGUCCAGAUCGGCAGGCUUCUCAUGGAAGAGCUGGUGAAUUUCAUUGAAAGAGUGCCAAAGGCUCAGUCUGCCUCCUUGUGGAAGAAUAAGGACAUUCAGAGGCUGUUACCUUCUCCUCUCAAGGAUGCAGUGGAAGUCUCAACCUGGAGAAGAUGCUAUACAAUGCAAGAGGUGAACUCUGCCCUUAGUAAAAUCCAGCUGGUGGGAUAUUCUCAGAAAAUUGAGCUUUUUGGUGCGGUCCAGGUGACUCCUCUGAGCUCUGGCUAUGCCCUUGGGAGCUCCAACUGGAUCAUCCAGUCUCAUUACGAGAAAGUGUCUUAUGUCUCUGGAUCCUCCUUGCUUACCACACACCCCCAGCCCAUGGACCAAGCUUCUCUCAAAAACAGCGAUGUUCUUGUUCUGACAGGGCUUACCCAGAUCCCCACUGCAAACCCAGAUGGAAUGGUGGGAGAGUUCUGCAGCAACCUAGCUCUGACAGUCCGGAAUGGAGGAAACGUGUUGGUUCCCUGCUACCCUUCUGGAGUGAUCUAUGACCUCCUGGAGUGCCUAUAUCAGUACAUCGACUCAGCCGGGCUUUCCAGCGUCCCCCUCUACUUCAUCUCCCCUGUGGCCAACAGUUCACUGGAGUUUUCCCAGAUCUUUGCUGAGUGGCUUUGUCACAACAAACAGAGUAAGGUGUAUCUUCCAGAACCACCUUUUCCUCAUGCAGAGCUCAUUCAGACCAAUAAGCUGAAGCACUACCCCAGCAUCCACGGAGACUUCAGCAACGACUUUAGACAGCCCUGUGUGGUGUUCACCGGGCACCCUUCCCUCCGCUUCGGGGACGUGGUCCACUUCAUGGAGCUCUGGGGAAAAUCUAGUCUCAAUACCGUCAUAUUCACGGAACCAGACUUCUCCUACCUGGAAGCCCUGGCUCCUUACCAGCCGCUGGCCAUGAAAUGCAUCUACUGCCCCAUCGACACCCGGCUGAACUUCAUCCAGGUGUCAAAGCUGCUUAAAGAAGUGCAGCCCCUGCACGUGGUGUGUCCUGAGCAGUACACUCAGCCGCCCCCAGCCCAGUCCCACAGGAUGGACCUCAUGAUCGACUGCCAGCCCCCCGCCAUGUCCUAUCGGCGGGCUGAGGUUCUCGCCCUGCCCUUCAAACGUCGGUACGAGAAGAUCGAGAUCAUGCCAGAGCUCGCAGAUUCACUGGUGCCCAUGGAGAUCAAGCCUGGCAUCUCCUUGGCAACUGUCUCGGCCGUGCUGCACACCAAAGAUAACAAGCACUUGCUUCAGCCCCCUCCUCGGCCCGCCCAGCCCACGAGCGGGAAGAAGAGAAAGCGGGUGAGCGAUGACGUACCAGACUGCAAAGUCCUGAAGCCUUUGUUGAGCGGUUCCAUCCCUGUGGAGCAGUUCGUGCAGACCCUGGAGAAGGUCCUGCUGGGAGACCCAGGAGAAAGAAAGCAGAGUGAGGAGUGCCCCAUCCUUCCUCCCAGCACGAGGUCACCAGAAGGCCUCUCCAGACUGAAGAAAAAGCUGCUUCCACACACACAUGUGACGAGUGGGGCAGGGUAGUGAGGCCAGGACAAAGAGGGACCCGGCCCUGCCAGAGUCUUGCACUUCCACAGAUGACUCCUUGCUGUCAGAGGGGAGCCAAGUCUCCAGUCGACUGUCAGGAUUUGCAGGAGGCAGUCGGGGGAGGGGACACUGGCCCUUCCCCUCUGUCUCAGCAGCCCUGAUGGCUGCUUCUCCCAGAGAUGAGAUUUCUUGACUAUGAUUAAAAGAAAAAAAUCUAACCUUAAAGGUUGUAAUUUUGGCUUCAGUCACAGGACUUCAGAGAUGACUUUAUUAGGAUUAUAGAAUCUUUGAUAGGAAGAAGGAAUUGGCUAAAGGUAAUACUGUUCAUGCUGCUGCUUGCAAGAACUGCAACAAAUUACAAUCAUUACAAGGAAGGAGAUUUCUAUGAACUUUCUAUCCAAUGUAAAUAUCACAGUUGCCGACUUUCAAAUCUUAAAGGCUUUCCCUUUCCUAGGAUUGGUUUUCUCCACCUGUCUUUGAUUUUCCCGUAGGGAAAAAGGCUCUGGCUGGGUGGUUGCGGCUCUCUUCCACCCUCCCUGAAGACCUUGCAGGGCUCCUGGGCCCUGUUAAUGGGCCUCAAGCUGGACUUUUAAAAACUUAAGAUGAGGACCUUCUGCCUGGCCCAGCCUAUGUCCUGACCCAGUGUUCCACCCCGGCUCCUCUCUGCAGAAGGAGCAAGCACCUGUCCAAGUCCCUAGGGGAGCCUGCAGCCAUGAAGUACAGGUGGCCUCCCCACACCGAGGCCCUUCACCUGCUGUGUGUCUGUUUCAGGCACAUGCCUCCUUUCCAUGUCACGUCUGAUUUGUAAGGAAUUUCUGUCCUUAGCAUUAGCAAUAGCUGAGAAGUUUGCACUGCUGCCUUCUCUCCUUCACUCUUGAGAGGGCUCUGCCAAGUCCCACAGGGGUAUCUUGGUGUCACCUGGCAUUUUCCUGGGAGCUCAGACAGCUGAAACUUAGGAGGGAGCUGUCACCAGGGAACGGCAUGGUGCAAGCAGCUGAGCGUCCCAGACUCCUGAACACAGUGCUUGGACGUGCCCUCAAAGAACUCACAAAAGCUUAGCCAGGUUGUGGAAAUUCUGUUGUUUUGCAUGAGCUUUUGCAUGUUUAGGGUCUCUUUUCAAGUAUAAGAAACUAUCACUAUCAUAGGCCUAUGACUAGUCUGAAGAAUUGUGUUGAGACGUGUCAGUUUCUAGAAAGUUCAGUCGAGUCUGUGAAGUGUCAUUUACAGAUCUCACAGAUGUGCAGUCUGCCCAGCCCACCUCUUUCUUUUCUUCUGGAGCAGCAUGGCUUCAGUGAUAUUAAGGUGGAGGACACAGCCAAGGGCCAUAUCGUCCUGCUCCAGGAGGCUGAGACGCUCAUCCAGAUUGAAGAAGACUCGACCCAUAUCAUCUGCGACAAUGACGAGAUGCUCAGAGUGCGACUGCGGGACCUUGUCCUCAAAUUCUUACAGAAGUUCUGAGUGGGCCAUCUGAGCUACUUCCCUGAAAUCCUGCAGUCCCUCACUGGCUGCCCUCACAAGCCACCUGAGGAGUGGCAUGAGAGGCCAUUAACUGUGUCUUUGUGGUGUCCUCUGGCUUAAGGAGUGAAGAGGUGGCUCUUGAGGGAAAUGGUCUGGACUUAUUCCCAGCACUGUUUCAGGCAAGAACUUUCCCUUUCAACUUCAGGCUCAUUUUCUUCUCAACUCUGGCUCUCUCAAGGAGCUGGAGGGUGGCAGAAGUGGGACAGGAGAAGUUUUCCAAGAGGUUCAUGGGAGGCGGAGGUGACUGGCUGGCUGUCUUGCAUCAGUCCCAGGCCUCGGCCAGGGGAGCCAGCCUUUGGUUUCGUUUACUUGCCUACAGUGCUGUACGCAAUAAGAUGAUGAUCCCAAAAUAUGGUAAAGUGAACCCAUCUGUCUGCAUUUUCUACUCUGAGCCCAUUUGUUAAUAAACACUUAUUUUUAUAUAA